CCAAACGCCGAGCGAGCGAGGGAGAGGCACAGUCAGAGGGAACGCCCGCGCGGGGAGCCAGGGGCGCCCGACCCCGCCGCCGCCGCAGCGGCGCGCAGCCCCCGACGCGCCCUGUGGGGACCCGGACCAGGAGGGACCCUGCCCCGGGAAAAGGCUGUGGAGACCUGGGCUCCGACCCCAGUUCAUCCCCCCACACCCCCGCCGCCCCGUGCCACCCUGGUCCGCGCUGGGAACCCUAUCCUGCCCCUCGUGUCAGCCCGGCACUGGCCAGAAUCGCGGGCAUGGCGGUGACCAUGCUGCAGGACUGGUGCCGGUGGAUGGGGGUCAACGCUCGCAGGGGCCUGCUCAUCCUGGGCAUCCCGGAGGACUGUGAUGAUGCCGAAUUCCAAGAGUCCCUCGAGGCUGCCCUGAGGCCUAUGGGACACUUUACAGUGCUAGGCAAAGCGUUUCGAGAGGAGGAUAAUGCCACCGCGGCCCUGGUCGAGCUCGACCGGGAAGUCAACUAUGCUUUGGUCCCCAGGGAAAUCCCCGGCACUGGGGGCCCGUGGAACGUGGUCUUUGUGCCCCGUUGCUCAGGCGAGGAGUUUCUCGGUCUCGGUCGCGUGUUCCACUUCCCGGAGCAAGAGGGGCAGAUGGUGGAGAGCGUGGCCGGCGCCCUGGGUGUGGGGCUGCGCAGGGUGUGCUGGCUGCGAUCCAUCGGUCAGGCGGUCCAGCCCUGGGUGGAGGCCGUGAGGUGCCAGAGCCUGGGCGUGUUUUCCGGGAGGGACCAGCCAGCCCCAGGGGAGGAGUCCUUUGAGGUCUGGCUAGACCACACCACCGAAAUGCUGCAUGUGUGGCAGGGGGUCUCGGAAAGGGAGAGGAGGAGGAGGCUGCUGGAAGGCUUGCGUGGGACCGCCCUGCAGCUCGUGCACGCGCUCCUGGCGGAGAACCCCGCCAGGACGGCGCAGGACUGUCUGGCGGCCCUGGCCCAGGUGUUUGGAGACAACGAGUCCCAGGCGACCAUCCGGGUGAAGUGUCUGACCGCUCAGCAGCAGUCAGGCGAGCGUCUCUCAGCUUUCGUGUUGCGGCUGGAAGUGCUGCUGCAGAAGGCCAUGGAGAAGGAGGCCCUGGCCAGAGCAUCCGCCGACCGCGUGCGCCUGAGGCAGAUGCUCACCAGGGCCCACCUUACUGAGCCUCUGGAUGAAGCACUGAGGAAGCUGAGAAUGGCCGGGAGGUCUCCAAGUUUCUUGGAGAUGCUGGGGCUCGUUCGGGAGUCUGAGGCAUGGGAGGCCAGUCUAGCCAGGAGCGUGAGAGCCCAGACACAGGAAGGGGCCGGUGCCCGGGCUGGUGCCCAGGCUGUUGCCAGAGCCAGCACUAAAGUAGAGGCGGUCCCAGGAGGUCCUGGUCGGGAGCCAGAGGGCCUCCUCCAGGCAGGAGGCCAGGAGGCUGAGGAGCUCCUCCAGGAGGGGCUCAAGCCCGUCCUGGAGGAAUGUGAUAACUAGGUUGGGGCUGGGGAGGCAGCCCAGCGCGAGUCCUCCCCGGGCAAAUAGGCUCCGAGGGCCCCGGGGCCUCCUCUCCUCCUCUCAGGCAGCAGGGCCCUGGAGACAGGCGGAGGCGGGGCCAGGGCCGGUCCCUCACCCCACAUCGGGAUCGGGGCCCCCCACUUCCCCCCAAGGGGCCCUGCCCACCACCACCUUCCCGGUGACCCAGAUGACCACAUUUAAUACCAAAUGGGGUGGGGGGAGGCGCCCCUCCAGUGCCAGGGGCACGUGCUGUGAGCUUCCUGGGAGCCCAGGUUGUGCUCACUGCUCUCCCGUAUCGUGAGCACCACCUCUGCUUUCCCUGCGUAGAUCUAGGCCAGGGGCUGCUUGUUUUUGUGGAGCCGUGUGUGUUCUUCUCUGAGCAGCUCCUCCCCAGAGGACCCCAGCGCAGUCCCGGGAGAUGGCGGAAAGAAGGCACCAGGGCACAGUGGACACUCAUCCCGUGACAGCGAUGGUGACCAUGACUGUGGGAGAAAGAACAGGACCCGGGAUGGAGUGGGGCUGUCUGAGUUUCCCCAGUGAACUUUGUGCUUUGGCGUUCCACCCCUGUUGUUACUUGUUACUGAGUUUCCUAGACCUGGGGUGGGUGUUCCCCCAGGAGGAGGGGGGUCCCGACCUGUGUCCUGUGGUGGCCAUUUGCAGCUUCUGUGUUGUGAUUCCCUUCUCUUCAACGGUUUCAGUACAUAUCUCUCUUCAAUAAAUUUCAUUCAGUGUUCCA